GUCAGAAUCACCAUGGCCAGCUAUCCUUACCGGCAGGUGAGUGUGUGAGGGGCCCGCGAAUCCAGGUAGCGGCGGUGCCAGGCGCAGGCCCGACGUCCCCCUGCUCUUUCUCCCCGCUUUCUCCGCGCCCUUCCCACGAUGGGUUCGCUUCAGCGAGGCCUUGCGCUGUAGAGAACCGAAAAGGGACCGUCGGUCGCGCCCUGCUCACGUCAUGAAGGACCGCACAUUCGCGAGGUCGUGUCGCGCCCCCUUGACGUCGCUCACUCGAGGAUUUGGGGACCUUGGACCCCACAGGUCCAGGCUGGCGCUGGCCUGGGCUCCACAGCCUCCCAAGGCCCUCAUGGGGGCCUUGGGCGGGGGCAUCAGCCAUGACCGGAGGUUUAGAGUUCUGGUUCCGCCGAUCUCAUUUGGGGCGUCGGAUAAAAAUCCAGGCUUCCGGACCCACCCCACACUGCAUCAGAGUCAUCAGGAAACUCUGGUUGUAGCAGGCGCCACAAGUGAGCUGGUUUGACCACUGACUUAGUUCAACACCGCCAUUUCGCGUGUAGAAAAGUGAACCCCGAGAAGACACAGAACUUACCUGAAGUCACCAGGCAGUUAGGCAGCAGGGCCGAGGUCAGAACCCGGGCUAUCUUCAGAUGCCUCUUCCCCAGCGUAUCUUGAUUCAGUCAGGAAUACCGCAGCAAGGUGAUUCUGUGGCCAGAAUUCUUUGUUGGGUGAUAGUAGGGUGUUGAAGUGCACUUUGGUGUCAGAGGUAGGUUCAUAUCUUAGCUCUACCACCUAAAUAGUUGUGAGCCCUUGAGCAAGCUGUUUUGCCUUUCUGAGUCCAAGUUUCCGCCUGUAAAAUAGGGCCGAAUAAUAGGAUCUGCCUCAUAAAGCUGUUGUGGAGAGUCAGGAGGUGAUGCUUACGAAGCGUUUGGUACAUAGUGAGGUGUAACAUGUGUUGCCCUUUAGCAUUUUGAUUUUUAGUAGACUUCUAAAAGGCCAGUGCCCGGAGGGUCCUCAAAAUAGAGCCCUCAUUUUACAGAGGAGGAAAUGAAGCCCACAGAGGGCUGCGAUCACACAGUUAUUUAGGAGAUGAAAUCCAUAAACGAAAUGUGGGAAAACAAGAUCAAUUGGUAUAUUACACAGUGCUCAACUGAGUUUAGUCACAGGCCAAAAGAUGUAACAGUCCUUCCAGGGAGUGCAGUCUUGUGCGGGUUACACAGUGUUUGGACCUCCAUUAUCCUAAUCAUGAAGUCCCUAUCGGCAUGCAGGUAUUAUUACCCCUAAUUAACUGCUGAGGAGCAAACCCAAAGAGGUUAAGUGGCUUCCCAAAAGUCACACGUAGUAAGUGAGGGUGAGGCCAUGACCAGAGCUUAGGACUUCUCUUAUUGCAUCCUUAGAGAGAGGUAGGAAAGAGAGAGGCCAGUGCGGGCUGGAGUUAGGAAGUGUAGCAUAGCAGUUGCUUCCUAAAGUCCAUUCCAUUUGCUGAGUCUUGGGAGGUUUUAAUAGAUAUUGUUAAUAUAGGAGGAUUCUGUAGUUAACUAAAGUUUUGGAAAUACUCUUAAGUAUAGCUGAAUAAGUUUAUUGACCACAAGCUAUUUCAGAAUCCUUAAUUUGCUAAUGUACAUUGUAAAUCAUCCAGAAAGGAAUAUAAUAUGCAGUAUUUCUUAAACAUAUCUAACCAUAGAAACUCCGCCUCCCGGCUUUCUUUUCAGAUGUCUGGUCACUUUUUUGACUCUAGUAUUUCUGAGGAACACAGGCUGAAAAAACAUUCAUAGCGCCUUGUUUCCCAGUGGCUGGUCUUCUGCCUCAGAAUCAGCUGAGAGCUUGUUUAAGAAAGCACACUUUUGGGUCCCACUUCAGACCUGUUCUGUACCCAGGAAUCUACAUGCUAAUAAGCAUUAGGGACAAUUGGUGUGCAUCCUAAAAGCAGUGACAGGUUAGAGAGAACUGUGCUAGAAUUCUAGCUGUAUUACUUAAUAGUUAUAUACCCCUGGACAAACUAAGGGCUCUGAGCCUCAGCUUCCUCACCUGUAUAAAGGGAGAAAUAAUACCUGUGAAAAGGGCUAAAAUGAGGUUAAAAUGCAGGGAGCCUGGCGUGUUGCUAGUGCCUAGUACAUGCCAGUGUCUGGUGGCAGCUCUUGCUGCCGUGACUGCUCUCAUGAUGCCAUGCUGCCUGGGCUAUUCCUGGAGUGAAAUACUGAAAAGGAGCACAGAGAGAAGAGUCUGGAAUAGAAAAAGAAAUGUUGUUUUUUUUUCCUACCAUACCCUUGUCCGCCUCCUGGUCUCAGGUGUUCUAAGAAAGGAAACGAGUUGUUUUAAAGCAUCUCAGUCAGUGCUGCCUCCCCUCCACCCACUACAUAGCUUUGGAGGAUUCCAGCCUAUUGUUAGGAGUCAGAAUUCCUGUAAUUUUCCACUGCUUCCAGUCCAGGGUACCCAAGCAGGGACUGGGUAUUGGAGUAGUAAAAUUCAAGCACCCUUUGGUCCUAUGGGGGAACGAGCUUGGUGGAUUUCAGUGCUUAAGAGCUUAGUUUUUGAGGCCAGAGAGAGUUGAUUUCAAAUCCCUGCUUUGUCACUCCCUUGCAGAAGUUUGUUGCAAAAGUCUGAGACUCAGUUUUCCCUUUUUUGAAAAAAAUUUUUUAUUUAUUUGUUUAUUUUUAAGACAGAGUCUUGCUCUGUCGCCCAGGCUGGAGUGCAAUGGCACAAUCUUGGCUCACUGCAACCUCCGUCUCCCGGGUUCAAGCAGUUCUCCUGCCUCAGCCUCCCAAGUAGCUGGAAUUACAGGCGCACGCCACCACACCUGGCUAAUUUUUUGUAUUUUUAGUAGAGACGGGGUUUCGCCAUGUUGGCCAGGCUGGUCUCAAACUCCUAACCUCAGGUGAUCCACCUGCCUCAGCCUCCCACAGUGUUGGGAUUACAGGCGUGAGCCACCACGCCUGGACUAGUUUUCCCUUCUUUAGAAUGGGGUCAUAAUAGUAUCUACCUCAGAAUUACUCUAAAGAUUAAAUGAGAAAAUCCACGUAAAGUGCUAGGUAUGGUGUUGGGCAUGUAGAAUACUCCAAGUGGAGGAGUAAUGCAGUUAUGCAGAUUGAAGAGGCAAUGUGAUAAGUAUUCAAUGGGAGUAAGUGUAAGGUACAGCACGGGAGAGUGAGAUACCUAACUCAGUCUAGGGGUGCAUUUUUAAAAGAGGUGAUAUUUAAGCCAACAACUGAAUCACUGGUAGAAAUUAGCUGAGUGAAGAAAGGAAUGCUAUUCCAGCAGAGGAAAUAGCUGCACAAAGCCCAUGAAGCAGGGCUGCCCAGGAGCUGCAGGACAAGCACCAGGAGCCCCUCCGGGUAGCUACUACCCUGGACCCCCCAAUAGUGGAGGGCAGUAUGGUAGUGGGCUACCCCCUGGUGGUGGUUAUGGGGGUCCUGCCCCUGGAGGGCCUUAUGGACCACCAGCUGGUGGAGGGCCCUAUGGACACCCCAAUCCUGGGAUGUUCCCCUCUGGAACUCCAGGAGGACCAUAUGGCGGUGCAGCUCCCGGGGGCCCCUAUGGUCAGCCACCUCCAAGUUCCUACGGUGCCCAGCAGCCUGGGCUUUAUGGACAGGGUGGCGCCCCUCCCAAUGUGGAUCCUGAGGCCUACUCCUGGUUCCAGUCGGUGGACUCAGAUCACAGUGGCUAUAUCUCCAUGAAGGAGCUAAAGCAGGCCCUGGUCAACUGCAAUUGGUCUUCAUUCAAUGAUGAGACCUGCCUCAUGAUGAUAAACAUGUUUGACAAGACCAAGUCAGGCCGCAUCGAUGUCUACGGCUUCUCAGCCCUGUGGAAAUUCAUCCAGCAGUGGAAGAACCUCUUCCAGCAGUAUGACCGGGACCGCUCGGGCUCCAUUAGCUACACAGAGCUGCAGCAAGCUCUGUCCCAAAUGGGCUACAACCUGAGCCCCCAGUUCACCCAGCUUCUGGUCUCCCGCUACUGCCCACGCUCUGCCAAUCCUGCCAUGCAGCUUGACCGCUUCAUCCAGGUGUGCACCCAGCUGCAGGUGCUGACAGAGGCCUUCCGGGAGAAGGACACAGCUGUACAAGGCAACAUUCGGCUCAGCUUCGAGGACUUCGUCACCAUGACAGCUUCUCGGAUGCUAUGACCCAACCAUCUGUGGAGAGUGGAGUGCACCAGGGACCUUUCCUGGCUUCUUAGAGUGAGAGAAGUAUGUGGACAUCUCUUCUUUUCCUGUCCCUCUAGAAGAACAUUCUCCCUUGCUUGAUGCAACACUGUUCCAAAAGAGGGUGGAGAGUCCUGCAUCAUAGCCACCAAAUAGUGAGGACCGGGGCUGAGGCCACACAGAUAGGGGCCUGAUGGAGGAGAGGAUAGAAGUUGAAUGUCCUGAUGGCCAUGAGCAGUUGAGUGGCACAGCCUGGCACCAGGAGCAGGUCCUUGUAAUGGAGUUAGUGUCCAGUCAGCUGAGCUCCACCCUGAUGCCAGUGGUGAGUGUUCAUCGGCCUGUUACCGUUAGUACCUGUGUUCCCUCACCAGGCCAUCCUGUCAAACGAGCCCAUUUUCUCCAAAGUGGAAUCUGACCAAGCAUGAGAGAGAUCUGUCUAUGGGACCAGUGGCUUGGAUUCUGCCACACCCAUAAAUCCUUGUGUGUUAACUUCUAGCUGCCUGGGGCUGGCCCUGCUCAGACAAAUCUGCUCCCUGGGCAUCUUUGGCCAGGCUUCUGCCCUCUGCAGCUGGGACCCCUCACUUGCCUGCCAUGCUCUGCUCGGCUUCAGUCUCCAGGAGACAGUGGUCACCUCUCCCUGCCAAUACUUUUUUUAAUUUGCAUUUUUUUUCAUUUGGGGCCAAAAGUCCAGUGAAAUUGUAAGCUUCAAUAAAAGGAUGAAACUCUGGA